CUCUUUUCCUCCUUGGCUGUCUGAAGAUAGAUCGCCAUCAUGAACGACACCGUAACUAUCCGCACUAGAAAGUUCAUGACCAACCGACUACUUCAGAGGAAACAAAUGGUCAUUGAUGUCCUUCACCCCGGGAAGGCGACAGUGCCUAAGACAGAAAUUCGGGAAAAACUAGCCAAAAUGUACAAGACCACACCGGAUGUCAUCUUUGUAUUUGGAUUCAGAACUCAUUUUGGUGGUGGCAAGACAACUGGCUUUGGCAUGAUUUAUGAUUCCCUGGAUUAUGCAAAGAAAAAUGAACCCAAACAUAGACUUGCAAGACAUGGCCUGUAUGAGAAGAAAAAGACCUCAAGAAAGCAACGAAAGGAACGCAAGAACAGAAUGAAGAAAGUCAGGGGGACUGCAAAGGCCAAUGUUGGUGCUGGCAAAAAGAUGAGGGAAUUGGGGCUUGGAGUGCAAGCAUUGGGAAGAAUUUCCCAGGAAGAGAGAUGCACAGAUGUGAAGAACUCGAAGGCAAGAGAAAGCCGGGGGGUUGUGUGGCAGGUAGAAGUGCCAGGACCGUGGAGCGUGUGGACAUGUGGCAGAUUGCGGAGGGGCUGUGGCAAGUAUUUACAGGUGGCCGUUACCUGGAGGAAGACUGAAAACAGAGAACAGUGCUGCCAGGCGUGCCUUUUGGAGAGGGCACUGGUCAGAAACGGAGCCUUCAUGUCGCCUGCCUCACCUGCUCCUGCUGGUUCUCCCCACCCUGUGGACGGUGACUUGGUCCUCCACUUGCCAGAAGCCUUGUCAGCAACCUUGACUCUGUCACCCCACAUCCAGGCCAUCAACAAGUCUUUUGGCCCUUUCUUUGAAAUCCACCAGGAAUCCAGCUGCUUCUCCCCACCUUCCUGCCUCUCUGGUCUGGGCCACUAAUGUCACUGCCAUGGCCGCCUUGCUGCAUUUCUGAGGAUGCUUCAUCUCUCCACCUUCUUCUCCACUCAGCAGCCAGCAGGGCACUGUGGAAAUCGGAGUCACAUGAGCUGGCACCUCUGUUCAGAACCCUCCAGGGCUCCACAUCUCUCUCACCCAAAUGCCAAAGACCUCCCCACGCCCCCACAAUCCCCCACGACCUGGCCACUGGCCUCCCACCACCUUCCAGCUCCAGCGGCUCCUACCACAUUUAAGGCUUUCCUUCCUAGUUUUAAUUUUUCCUCGUCAGCAGUUGAUUUUAUUAUUUUCUUGUUUAUUGGUAUUUUCCCACUAGAAAUGAAGCUGCGUGAAGUUAGAGAUUUUUUUUUUUGGUCUGUGUUCCUAAUUAGCUCAUUGCUAUACCCCUGGCGCCCAGAACAAUGCCUUGGACACAGUACGCAGUAGACUAAAUAAAUACUUGUUGAAUGACUGACUGACGGAAUGACGGCUGUGUGGGGAGUGGAUUGGGUCGUGAGGCAGAGGCUGCGGUGGAAACUCAGGCAGGAGGUGAUGGUGGUUCUUGGGGCUGCGGAAUGCCAAGUUUAGAAGCUCUUCCUCUGCUGUGGCACAUGAACCGGUCACUCGAGAAGGCUUUUAGAUUUACUUUGCCUAAUCCCCUCUUAGUGCAUGUGGGGAAACUGAGGUACACAAAAGGAAUUCCCCACCAAGUUAGGGGCAGAACCUAGCCCCCUUGUCUCCCAGAUGGAUAUCUUCUUUUUUUUUUGAGACGGAGUCUUGCUCUGUUGCCCAGGCUGGAGUGCAGUGGUACCAUCUUGGCUCACUGCAACCUCUGCUUCCCAGGUUCAAGCGAUUCUCCUGCCUCAGCCUCCUGAGUGUCUGCGAUUACAGGUGCACACAACCACGCCUGGCUAAUUUUUGUAUUUUUAGUAGAGACGGGGUUUCACCGUGUUGGUCAGGGUGACCUCAAACUCCUGACCUCAUGAUCCACCCAGCUCAGCCUCCCAACGUGCUGGGAUUACAGGCAUGAGCCACCGUGCCUGGCUGGACAUCUUGUUAUUAAAGCUUCUUCUCUCUUUGUAGGGGAGGGGGAGAUGCCUCUGGUGGAGAAGACCAGUGUGGCAGUGACUGUGUCUGUUAGUGAACCUGGUGGCUGGUUGAGGGUCUGUCGUGGUGACUGAGGACACAUACAAAGUGCUUUUCUCAGUGGUCACCUUGGUGUUGGUGAAUAAGGGUCAGAAGAUGGCUCCUGUCCUAGGGCACUGCCAGUCGGUUUGGAAGCUGAAAUGCCUGCUUAGCAGUUUGAGGAAACACAGACCUUGGAGGAUCUUCUGGUUGCCUCUUCAAGAAUUCAUUCUAUUCCCCUUCUGCUCCCCAAAUUUGCUUUUCUUGGGGUGGGUCUUGGUUGGCCUAAGCCAAGAAAGUAUGGCAUCUACUCCUUCCAUAGCAAUAGCUCAGGAAUAGGCAGUGACCCAGACCUGAACCAAUCAGUGCAUGGAAUUACCCCUGGCCAAAGUGGUUGAUUGAGGCUGGGUGCAAGCAGAGUUGUGAGAAGGCUCCCAUUUGGUGGUUGGAGAGAUCGCACUUGCUCCAGAGGUCAUAAUGUGCAGAUCUGAGGCUUGGAACUGCUGCAGACAUUUUGCUACCACAAGUGAAGCCACCCUGACGACACAGUUGACAAUUUGGAGCAGGGCAGAGCUGAGAGAACAGCAGGGAAACAGCCAGAGUCUUGCUCAAGCCUCCCUGAAGUAUCUAUACCCCUGGACUCUAGUUAUGGGGGCUAAUAAAUGUUAUAUACUGUU